AUUCUUGAAGGUUAGAGCUCAGCUUUGAAGUUUCACUUCACGAGCUUGGCUCAGUGAGGAAAUUGUGACGUGUGUUCUGGGCAGGGUUUGAGGUUUUGGAACAUUUUCUAAAAGGGACAGAGAGCACCCUGCUACAUUUCCUAAUCAAGAAGUUGGCGUGCAGCUGGGAGAGCUAGACUAAGUUGGUCAUGAUGCAGAAGCUACUCAAAUGCAGUCGGCUUGUCCUGGCUCUUGCCCUCAUCCUGGUUCUGGAAUCCUCAGUUCAAGGUUAUCCUACGCGGAGAGCCAGGUACCAAUGGGUGCGCUGCAAUCCAGACAGUAAUUCUGCAAACUGCCUUGAAGAAAAAGGACCAAUGUUCGAACUACUUCCAGGUGAAUCCAACAAGAUCCCCCGUCUGAGGACUGACCUUUUUCCAAAGACGAGAAUCCAGGACUUGAAUCGUAUCUUCCCACUUUCUGAGGACUACUCUGGAUCAGGCUUCGGCUCCGGCUCCGGCUCUGGAUCAGGAUCUGGGAGUGGCUUCCUAACGGAAAUGGAACAGGAUUACCAACUAGUAGACGAAAGUGAUGCUUUCCAUGACAACCUUAGGUCUCUUGACAGGAAUCUGCCCUCAGACAGCCAGGACUUGGGUCAACAUGGAUUAGAAGAGGAUUUUAUGUUAUAAAAGAGGAUUUUCCCACCUUGACACCAGGCAAUGUAGUUAGCAUAUUUUAUGUACCAUGGUUAUAUGAUUAAUCUUGGGACAAAGAAUUUUAUAGAAAUUUUUAAACAUCUGAAAAAGAAGCUUAAGUUUUAUCAUCCUUUUUUUUCUCAUGAAUUCUUAAAGGAUUAUGCUUUAAUGCUGUUAUCUAUUUUAUUGUUCUUGAAAAUACCUGCAUUUUUUGGUAUCAUGUUCAACCAACAUCAUUAUGAAAUUAAUUAGAUUCCCAUGGCCAUAAAAUGGCUUUAAAGAAUAUAUAUAUAUUUUUAAAGUAGCUUGAGAAGCAAAUUGGCAGGUAAUAUUUCAUACCUAAAUUAAGACUCUGACUUGGAUUGUGAAUUAUAAUGAUAUGCCCCUUUUCUUAUAAAAACAAAAAAAAAAAUAAUGAAACACAGUGAAUUUGUAGAGUGGGGGUAUUUGACAUAUUUUACAGGGUGGAGUGUACUAUAUACUAUUACCUUUGAAUGUGUUUGCAGAGCUAGUGGAUGUGUUUGUCUACAAGUAUGAUUGCUGUUACAUAACACCCCAAAUUAACUCCCAAAUUAAAACACAGUUGUGCUGUCAAUACCUCAUACUGCUUUACCUUUUUUUCCUGGAUAUCUGUGUAUUUUCAAAUGUUACUAUAUAUUAAAGCAGAAAUAUAACCAAA